UGGAUACUAUAUUGGUUUUCUAGGGCUGUUGUAAUAAAGUAUUAUAAACUGAGCAGCUUAAAACAACAGAAAUUAUCCGGGCACAGUGUAUCAUGCCUGUAAUCCCAGUACUUUGGGAGACUGAGGGCGGGCAGAUCACUUGAGGUCAGGCGUUUGAGACCAGCCUAGCCAACAUGGUAAGAUCCUGUCUCUACUAAAAAUACGAAAAUUAGCCAGGCAUGGUGGCAGGUGACUGUAGUCCCAGCUACUUGGGAGGCUGAGGCAGGAGACUCACUUGAGCCCAGGAGGUGGAGACUGCAGUGAGCCAAGAUCAUGCCACUGCACUCCAGCCUGGGUGGCAGAGGGAGACUCCACCUCAAAACAAACAAGCAAAAACAGAAAUGUAUUCUCUCGCAGAUGUGGAGGCUAGAAGUUAGAAAUGAAGGUAUCAGCAGGACCAGCUUCCUCUGUAGGCCCCUUGGUUUCUUGUUCUAGCUUCUGGUGGUUGCCAGUCAUCCUUGGUGUUUCUUGGCUUGUAGAUGCAUCACUUGAAUCUCUCUGCCUCCAUCAUCACAUGGCCUUCUUCCCAAGUAUUUUAUCUGCAUCUUCAAAUAUCUCUCUCCUUAUCAGAUUACCAGUCAUUGGAUUUAGGGCCCACUCUAAUCCAGUAUGCCUUCAUUUUAACUUGAUUACAUCUGUAAAGGCUCUCAAAGAAGGUCACAUUCACAGGUACAGGGGAUUCAAACUUUAACAUAUAUAUUUGGUGGGGUGGGGACACAAUUUAACUCACAACAGGUAUGACAGAUAACUUUGGGAGGAGAAGCACCUGGUGAAUGGGUAGGAAGGGAGGGGUCAAUCAAGGUAACCAAAGAAAAAAAUAAAUGAGGAUGGGAAAGAAUACAGUAAAAAUACCUUCAUAAGAAUAAAUUGCCCUGUUAAUAUAAAAUUCUGUGCAUGUGUAUGAAUAAAUUAGAAUAAAGAGCUAGCUCUGUAUUAAUUUGUAGGCAUAACAUUCGAUAAUUCUUUUAUAUGGUUUAUUGUGUGCCAGGCACUGUUUUAAGCACUUUCCAUACAUUAACUCCUUUAAUCCUUAUGUCUCAACCCAUGAUAUAGGUACUAUUAUUAUUACACCCAUUUUACUGAUGAUGAAACUGAGACAUAGAGAGACAUAGCUAGUAAAAUGGCUGAGCCAGGAUUCAAACCUGAGCCAUCGGGCUUCAGAAUCUGUGCUCUUAAUCACCUUGGCAUAUGUAGUAUGACUCUGUUCUUCAGAAACUAAAACAAUAUAUAUGUGUACAAAUGCAUAUGUAUACAUUUAUAUUUUAGAAGACAUAAAAUUAAAGUAUCAAGAUCAAAAAUAAAAUCUUGGAUUCUAACCAGCUCUGUCAGGGCUCACAGACAAUGAAUGAUAAAUAUUCUGGUUGGCCUAUUUUGUGUCAUAUACCCAGAUGCCCAGACUAGGUUUUUUUGGGGGGAGAAGGAGGGGCAUCAGUGCUUGGACAUUCUUGUCAGAGUCAUGUGGAGUGGGUUACUUAAAGGAAAGAGAUGAUCUAUUAUCAGAGGUAGGAGGAGAUGGCAGCUGACGGACUUGCAAAAACUAUAACUAGUCUGUCUCCUUGAACCUCAGUGUAACCUUCCCUACCUUUUUCUUAGAUGUAAACAGCAGAGCAGCUGAAGGUCCUUCACUCAUCAAACAAAAAGAAGGUAUGGCCCAAGGUGAAGAGAAAGGCUAUAGGGAAACCCUCCCCAAAACAUCACACCCAUUUUCCCAUGCCCUUUGUUCAGAAAAUAAUUAAUUGUGGAAAUGAGAUCUGUUGCCUCCCCACUUCCCCCAGCCCAGACCCGACAACAAUGGGGACCCUGUCUCUACUUCCUACAAGUCCACCAGGGGCAAAUUACCAUUUGGGGUUAUUUAAUGGUGUAAUAGGAGAAUCUGCUGCUUUUAGUUCAGGGGUGUCCAAUCUUUCAGCUUCCCUGGGCCAAACUGGAAGAAUUGUCUUGGGCUGCACAUAAAAUACAUUAACACUAAUGAUAGCUGAUGAGCUUAAAAAAAUUUGCAAAAAAAACCCAAAACCUCAAUGUUUUAAGAAAGUUUAUGAAUGUGUGUUGGGCCACAUUCAAAGCCAUCCUGGGCCACAUGAGGCCCAUGGGCUGUGGGUUGGACAAGCUUGAUUUAGAUCAUCUCGUGAUUUUAGGCUCUGCCAGUGUGGGGAUUAUCCCACCUGCAGGGAUUAUGUGGUGCUCUAGGAUUAUCUUGGGUUUGGGGUUGAUCCCCCCACAUGGAAGGAUUGUCUGGUGGUGCUAUCGGAUUAUCUUGGUUUUAGGGUUGAUCCCUCACAUGGAAGGAUUCUCUGCUACUUUGAUGUUCCUCAUGACCCGGUGCCGCCUGUUCUAUAGUAUCAACGUGUAAGUCCUUGACUCAGACCUAAUUCAAGGUAGGUUAAGGUGUCCUCCUGUCUACCAGUUCCUGUUUCAGGAACUUGGGAUGACCUUGUGAAGGGUAGGAAGUUUCUAUUUUCCUUUGAAGUGCUGUUCCAAGAGGUAAUAAUAGUGGAACUUGAGUUUCAGCAGUUGAUGAGAAUGGUGGCCCCUGUGUCUAAGAAGUAUGAGAAUUACAAUAUUGGGUAGCAGAGACUGAUAAAGAUGGUGAUAUAGGUUGAGCAUCCCUUAUCCAAAAUACUUGAGACAGAAAGUGUUUCAGGUUUGAUUUUUUUAUUUUGUAUUUUGGACUAUUUUCAUAUAUAUAAAAUCAGAUAUUUGGGGAUGAGACCCAAGUCCAAACACAAAAUUCAUUUGUUUUCAUUUCAUUUAUAUAUGCCUUCUACACAUAGCCUGAAGAUAAUUUUAUACAAUAUUUUUGUGCAUGAAACAAGGUUUUUUGUUUGUUUUAAGACAGGGUCUCACUCUAUCAACCAGGCUGGAGUGCAGCCUCAACUUCCUGGGCUUAAGCAAUCCUCCCACCUCAGCCUCCCUAGUAGCUGGGAGAAGAAGCAUGCAUCACCAUGCCCUGCUAAGUUUUAAAUUUUUUUAUUGUAGAGAUGGGAAUCCCACUAUGUUGCCCAGGCUGGUCUCAAAUUCCUGGGCUCAAGUGAUCCUCCUGCCUUAGCCUCCCAAACAGCUGGAUUACAGGCAUAAGCCACUGUGCCCAGCCCCAUGAAACAAAGUUUUGACUGCAAUCUAUCACAUGAGAUCAAGUGAUGGAAUGAAAUUUUUCACUUCUGACGUUACGUCGGUGCUCAAAAAGUUUUUGAUUUUGGAGCAUUUCAGAUUCGAGAUUUUUGCAUUAAGGAUGCUCAACCUGUACUUGUGUGCCAAUGUCUGAUGGGAAUGGUGGCCCCCUGUUUCAGGGAGUGAAGGCAAUGAUGGAUCCUGAGUUCUGGAUAUUUGUAGGAAUUGCAGUAGAUGAGUCUUAUGUGCUGAGAGAUUUGGAGCCCUGUAUUUCAGAGAAUGAAGGAACCAGUGGUCCCUGUGACUUGCUAACUGAUGAGAACAGAACAGAGGCCUUAUGUUUCAGAAACUAAUGGGAAUUAUGGUCACUGUUCCUGGGGGGCUUAAGCAAGUCCCAGCCUAAUCCACAAGUCAUUUAUUAUUCACUCAUCUCCUCAUUCAUUCACUUAGCAAACAUUUUCCUGAGCCCCUGCUCUGAGCCAUGCCUGGGUGGAGUGAUAUUGAGGACACAGAAAUGACUCAGACCCAGACUGUGCCCUCAGUAAAUUCCCAAAGACAGACCCAGACGUAGAAAAUCACAACACAACAGGAUCAGGGCCAGGACAAGGACUGUGAUGUGGUGCCUGUCCUGAUCUGUCUACAGGGCAUCCAGGGUGAAUGUAGAAUGACAGUAACUCUAGAUCGUAAGUGAAAGUGAGGGGUCUGACAAAGGGUCCUUCUUAAUCAUACAUGAAUUUGUGUGCAUGACAAGUUUAAAUGUACCCAGUGUCAAUCCUUAGAAAUAGCAUAUUUUCCCAGAGCAAGCCCACCCCAAAGAAGGAGCCAGAGAGGCCUGGGUUUGAAUCUCUAGCUCCAUCACAUACUUUGUGAGCUUGGGCAACUCGCUAUUCAGAACUGCAUCCUAUUCAGUAUUCCAUCCUUACAAUUGGGAUAAUAAUAGUUUCUAAUAAUAAGGUUUCUGUGUAAUCAAUGAUAUAAUGUAUAACAAAUACUCAUCCCAGGAACUGGCUCCAAGUAGUCAUUCAAUAAAGGGUAUCUGUUGUCAUUAUUAUUAUCCCAUUGUUAGUAAUUAUCAACAAAUUUUAAAGGAUCUAGAAGUAAGCAUUUAUCGAAUAUCUGGGUUUAGAGGCUUAAAAGCAUUGGACAAAAUCACUUUAAAAAUCAGCAAAUUUGGGCCAGGUGUGGUGGCUCAGCCAAGGUGGGAGGAUCACUUGAGGUCAGAAGUUCAAGACCAGUCCAGCAAACGUGGCAAAACCCCAUCUCUACAGAAUACACAAAAAUUAGCCGGGCCUGGUGGCGCAGGCCUGUAGUUCCAACCACGUGGGAGGCUGAGGUGGGAGAAUGGCUUGAACCUGGAAGGCAGAGGUUGCAGUGAUCUGAGAUAAUGCCACUGCACUCCAGCCUGGGCAAUCCGUCUCAAAAAUAAAUACAUACAUACAUACAUACAUACAUACAUACAUACAUACAUACAUAAGCAAAUCUGUAAAUAUCAAUAUGCAUAACCAUUAGUUUCUUGACAUAAAAAACCUCCCAAUCUCCCAAUUAACUGAAUACACUAGGAAUAAAUAGAUGAAUACAAUGGAAUAUUAUAUCACUAUUAAAAUGAAUGAGGAGGUUCUAUAAGCCUAGAUAUGGGAGGAUCUUUGGAUAUCAUGUAAAAAAAAAAAAAAAAACCAAGGUGCAGAAUAAUGUGAUCCUAUCAGGGGACAGAAAAGAGGAGGGUGGUAUAUAUGUGCAUAGAUGUAUAAAAUUCCUCUGGAAAGAUACAUAAGAAAUUAGUGAAUAUAUGCUGUCCCCAGAGAGGAGAACUGGGUGGCUGGAGGAUAGGGAGGGAGGGAGAUGCACUGUUGAAAGCCCAGCACCAUGCAUCCUGAACGUUUUCCCUGGCUCUUAAUGUCCACUAAGUUCUCAGAUGCCCACAGCAUCUCUCUCCUCUACCCUCUUCUUCCUCCUAGUUCCCCAUUGAAAGCAACUCCUGCCCCAUCCGUUCCUGGGCCAGACUCAGGGAGUUGUAGUUUUCCUACCUGUUUCCCGCCCACAGGUUCCUGUUCUCUGCCCCCAGUGCCCAGCAGUCUCCAGCCAUCUCCAGCUCCUCACAUUCCUGCCCCACCCCUUCCUCUCUCCCCAGGUCCUAGCCCGCAAACUGCAGGGAGGGGGCCUCCUCCCCAGCCUCCACCCGUCUCUCCCCCUCCACUCCACACAGCCUCAGCGGGGUCUGACAUUCAGCUAUAACCGUGUCCCCGCCCCUUGCUCACAACCUUCCAGGGCUCCCUGUCACCCUCAGAAGGCUAAGUUCCCAGCCUGGCCUGAAACUCCCUAAGAAUCUGACCCCGCCCGCUCGCCCCACCAGCCUCAUCUCCUGUGCUCCUUGGCUCCUGGCUUCGGAGGCUCUAGUCAGACUUAAGGGCUUUGUUGUCCUCCCAGCACCUCCUUGGUUUCCUGCCUUGGGCCUUCGCUUCAGCUGUGCCCUCUGCCUGGAAGGGCCUUAGUGGAGGUCAUGCCACAACCACGCCUUCUCUGGAGGUCCUCUCUGCCGUCUCCAGCUGCCAGGAUUCCUCCCGCCCUGGGCUCUCACAGCCUCUGGCCUCUCCCUGUGUCAUACCCAGAUCACCCGGGAUUGGGACUGUCUGCGGCUGGCUCUGUCUCUUCCAUCAGACUACUAUGAUGAGAGAAGCCACCUGCAUGACACCUUCACCCAGAUGACCCAUGCCCUGCAGGAGCUGGCUGCUGCCCAGGGAUCCUUUGAGGUUGCCUUCCCUGAUGCUGCGGAGAAAAUGAAGAAGGUCAUUACACAGCUUAAAGAAGCCCAGGCUUGCAUCCCUCCCUGCGGUCUCCAGGAGUUCGCCCGGCGUUUCCUCUGCAGCGGGUGCUACUCUAGGGUCUGCGACCUCCCGCUGGACUGCCCAGUUCAGGAUGUGACAGUGACUCGGGGCGACCAGGCUAUGUUUUCUUGCAUCGUAAACUUCCAGCUGCCAAAGGAGGAGAUCACCUAUUCCUGGAAGUUCGCAGGAGGAGGUCUCCGGACUCAGGACUUGUCCUAUUUCCGAGAUAUGCCGCGGGCCGAAGGAUACCUGGCGCGGAUCCGGCCGGCUCAGCUCACGCACCGCGGGACGUUCUCCUGCGUGAUCAAGCAAGACCAGCGCCCCCUGGCCCGGCUCUACUUCUUUCUUAACGUGACGGGCCCGCCCCCGCGGGCGGAGACAGAGUUGCAGGCCUCGUUCCGGGAAGUGCUGCGCUGGGCGCCGCGGGAUGCCGAGCUGAUCGAGCCCUGGAGGCCCAGCCUGGGCGAGCUGCUGGCCAGGCCCGAGGCUCUGACGCCCAGCAAUCUGUUCCUGCUUGCAGUCCUCGGGGCCCUCGCAUCAGCGAGUGCGACAGUGUUGGCGUGGAUGUUCUUUCGAUGGUACUGCAGUGGCAACUAACAAAGGUAUCUUUCCUCCUUCCCUAUCCUAUUUCCAUCCUGAAAAUAAAGAAUAUAUUUCAACUCUA